AGUGGCGAGGGGAGGAGCCGAGCCGGCACCGCGGCUGGCGCGCGGGGCUGCGGCGGCGGCGGCGGCGGCAGCGGCGGCAGCGGCGGCUCCGGCCCCUAGAUCAGACAUUCUCUCUCAUUACCCGGCGCGUGGGAACGGGUCCACAGCCCCUUGUCCGCCCUAGAACCCCCAUGGGCUGCCGCCCGCCGCCGCCUCGGCUGCCACCCAGGACACGGCAGAGAUAAGCGCAGCCCCUUCACUGCCCUUCUCCAUCUCUUCCUCCUUGUUCAUUUGUCCCUGUUCUCUGUCCUCUACUCCACUCAUGCCCAUCUCUGUCCCCUUGACUUACCCAGUCCCUGCUACUAUCUCCAUCCCUAAUUUCUGCCCUCUUGUCUGUCUACUCCUAAUUCCUUUUCCUUGUCCAUCCCUAAUACCUGUCACCUUGUCCUUCUUCCUCGAAUCUCCAUCCCUAAUCCAUCUGCCCCUAAUCUCUGUCCCCUUUGCCCAUCCUUCCUUUUCUCGGUGUCUCUUUCCACCCUUAUCUCCACACCUGCCCACCCUGCACUCCCAUUCUGUUUCCCAUCUGCACCCUUGCCCCAUCCCUCCCACACACAGGACCAGACGGCCACCAUGUCAGGAGACUACGAGGAUGACCUCUGCCGGCGGGCACUCAUCCUGGUCUCGGACCUCUGUGCGCGGGUCCGAGAUGCUGACACCAACGACAGGUGCCAGGAGUUCAAUGACCGAAUCCGAGGCUAUCCCCGGGGUCCAGAUGCAGACAUCUCCGUGAGCCUGCUGUCGGUCAUCGUGACAUUCUGUGGCAUUGUCCUUCUGGGUGUCUCUCUCUUCGUGUCCUGGAAGUUGUGCUGGGUGCCCUGGCGGGACAAGGGAGGCUCGGCAGUGGGCGGUGGCCCCCUGCGCAAAGACCUAGGCCCUGGUGUCGGGCUGGCAGGCCUGGUAGGCGGAGGCGGGCACCACCUGGCGGCUGGCCUGGGUGGCCAUCCUCUGCUGGGCGGCCCACACCACCAUGCCCAUGCCGCCCACCAUCCACCCUUUGCUGAGCUGCUGGAGCCAGGCAGCCUGGGGGGUUCUGACACCCCUGAGCCCUCCUACUUGGACAUGGACUCGUAUCCAGAGGCUGCAGCAGCAGCAGUGGCCGCUGGGGUCAAACCGAGCCAAACAUCCCCUGAGCUGCCCUCUGAGGGGGGAGCAGGCUCUGGGUUGCUCCUGCUGCCCCCCAGUGGUGGGGGCUUGCCCAGUGCCCAGUCACAUCAGCAGGUCACAAGCCUGGCACCCACUACCAGGUACCCAGCCCUGCCCCGACCCCUCACCCAGCAGACUCUGACCUCCCAGCCGGACCCCAGCAGUGAGGAGCGGCCACCUGCCCUGCCCUUACCCCUGCCUGGAGGCGAGGAAAAAGCCAAACUCAUUGGGCAGAUUAAGCCAGAGCUGUACCAGGGGACUGGCCCUGGUGGCCGGCGGAGCGGUGGGGGCCCAGGCUCUGGAGAGGCAGGCACAGGGGCACCCUGUGGCCGUAUCAGCUUCGCCCUGCGGUACCUCUAUGGCUCGGACCAGCUGGUGGUGAGGAUCCUGCAGGCCCUGGACCUCCCUGCCAAGGACUCCAACGGCUUCUCAGACCCCUACGUCAAGAUCUACCUGCUGCCUGACCGCAAGAAAAAGUUUCAGACCAAGGUGCACAGGAAGACCCUGAACCCCGUCUUCAAUGAGACGUUUCAAUUCUCGGUGCCCCUGGCCGAGCUGGCCCAACGCAAACUGCACUUCAGCGUCUAUGACUUUGACCGCUUCUCGCGGCACGACCUCAUCGGCCAGGUGGUGCUGGACAACCUCCUGGAGCUGGCCGAGCAGCCCCCUGACCGCCCGCUCUGGAGGGACAUCGUGGAGGGCGGCUCGGAAAAAGCAGAUCUUGGGGAGCUCAACUUCUCACUCUGCUACCUCCCCACGGCCGGGCGCCUCACCGUGACCAUCAUCAAAGCCUCUAACCUCAAAGCGAUGGACCUCACUGGCUUCUCAGACCCCUACGUGAAGGCCUCCCUGAUCAGCGAGGGGCGGCGUCUGAAGAAGCGGAAAACCUCCAUCAAGAAGAACACGCUGAACCCCACCUAUAAUGAGGCGCUGGUGUUCGACGUGGCCCCCGAGAGCGUGGAGAACGUGGGGCUCAGCAUCGCCGUGGUAGACUACGACUGCAUCGGGCACAACGAGGUGAUCGGCGUGUGCCGUGUGGGCCCCGACGCUGCCGACCCGCACGGCCGCGAGCACUGGGCAGAGAUGCUGGCCAAUCCCCGCAAGCCCGUGGAGCACUGGCAUCAGCUAGUGGAGGAAAAGACUGUGACCAGCUUCACAAAAGGCAGCAAAGGACUAUCAGAGAAAGAGAACUCCGAGUGAGGGGUCUGGCCUAGGCCCGGGAUCGGACCAGGCUCCCUCAGGACCCCAUCCUUUCCUGCCCGGACCGUGAAUUCAUCUCCUUGAAGCCAUAACGUCCGAGCUGCUGGUGCGGGGCAGCCCUGGCCCUAGGCUUCCUAACCCUGGAAGCGAGAGGAUGAGAGGAGGCCGGCCCAGCUCCUUCUUUCAGGGUGGGGGUCAUUCAGCCUCCACUGUGUCUGUCUUUUCUUCCCUGGGGCUCCCCCUCGAGGCGAGGGGCCAUGCAUGUCUGGGGGACCCCUGCCCCCCAAAACCCUCUGUCUGUCUCUGUCUCUUUGCUGUUUGUCCAAGACUCAGUGUCCCGACCCUUGUUCUCGCCGUGAAUGUCAAUGGGCCAAUCCUCUCUGUCCUUUCAGACACACACACACCUGUGUCCACCCCUUCUGUUCGCCACACCCCUGCGUCUGGCCGGUCCCCCCACUGCUGCUGCUAUCAACGCCAGAAUAAACACACUCUGUGGGUCUCACUCCAA